AGGGUGUGCCGUCCCGAGUGGAGCCGAGGCUCGGGACACGCAGGAAAGGACGCCGCCUGCCCGGGCUCCUGGAGACGCAGAACUUGGUGUGAGGUCUUGGGAAAACAGUUCAACCCGAUGUUUUAAGAGCCAGAAAAACAUUCCCACCCCUUGACCUGGUAACCCCACUGGUGGGGAUUUUCUCUUAGAGGGAUAAGAUACCGGGAAGGGGAGGUGAAAUGCUCACCACUGCCAAAACACGGGCUGCAACUGCAACAUCGGAGGAUGAGAGGGAGAGUCGGCUGUGGUGCAGAAUGCUCAGCAGCCCUCCCAGCAGGGACAGGAAGACUGGGCAGGAAGAGGGGAGAAGCAUUCAAGUUAAGGCAAAAGGCCCAACGCAGAGCAGCACACUGAGGUCACACCUGUGAGAUGUGGAAGAGAAUUCCUGAGCGUGGAGCGAUGGGGUUAGGUGCCAGGAUGAUUGCCCAUUUUGCUUCUGUCAGACUCUUGACUAAGGAUUUCUGGUUGCAUUUUAUUACAUAAAAGCCAGGGAGGUUAUAUCACGGUGAGAAAGCUUCCCUGACGCUGCCUCCUGUAGCGCAGCCAAGCGAGCCUGUGGAGGUACCAUAUGACUGUAGGCCUCUGGGGACAGGGAGCUGCAUCUGCUUCUCAAGGCCAGGGACACAGCCAUUUCUGCCAGCAUCUGUUGAUCAGUGAGUGAGUGAGUGGGCAGGUAGAGCAGGAGCCAGUGAAGAGCAGGCCCUGGAUGGGUGGGGAUGCACCAUGUCCCCAGGCUGCAGCUGCAGGCAGCCCCCCACAUUGUCGGAGAAGCCUCUGCACCAGCUCAGCCCCCUCCUCACUCCCCUUGUGCCCUGGGGACACUCUGCAGAGGGGCACUCUGCAGUCUGUCCCCGCCAUCGCUGGACUUCUGGACAUGGCCUCCAGAUUUGCACCUCUUAAAUAAAACUGCAGUGGAUGUCUUUGUGUGCACCUCUCUUUCCUUUUGGUGAGAAACAGCAAAGAUCGGACCCCUAAGGACUCUCCUGAUGUCUCCGCUCUAUCCGCUGAGUGCCCUUUCUGACCACUUGUUUGUACAGGCCACGGUCCAGGACGGGAGCAGAUAGACUGUCCCUGUCCCUGUCCACAUUUCCUUGGUCCAAACAGGGCUUGUGGGAGGUAGUGGCAAAAGGUGUUGGUCUUUUUCUCACUGAUUUGGAGGCCUCCCCGUGUGUUUUUUCAGCCGCGUGUUCCUGGGUCUUGCCUGGAUGGACAGGGUUUUUUAGCGCGUGGGAGCAGCUUUGCUGACCCAUGCCUGUUGCUUCCAGCCUGAUUCCCGAGAAGGGAGCCUGCUUGCGAAGGAACUGGCACUCGGGCCUGCCUGAAGGGGGCGCUGUCCAGACAACACCCAGCCUCCCGUCGUGGCAGGCGCUGUCGGAGCCAUGGAUGAUUGUGACCAAUAGGGGUGGUCGCCAGAGUUGAUUGUCCAGCCAGGCCCAGGGGCUGAGAGGAGGCUGUGUGGAGAGGUGGUUAGGAGCCAGGGCUCGGUCAGCUGAGUUCGCAUGCCAGCUUCCUAGCUGUGGGACCUCAAGCAACUUGUAGCCCCUCUGAAGCUGUUUUCUCAACUGUGAAGUGGACGCACCCUACUUCAUUGAUUCUAAGAGGCACGCAUUUCCACCUUGUGACUUCUCUGAAACUGAGGUGCGUCUUUCAGUCAGUGGCGUCUCAUAGUCGCUGUCAGCCAGCUGGUAUUCGAGAUGGAGUCGUGGAAAACCCGUGGACACCUUCCGCUAGGACCAAGAUGGCGCCACCUGCCGCAUCUUAGAUUUGAUGAAAUGUGGAAUCAUGUUCGUUCAGGAGGAGGCCCUGGCCAGCAGCCUCUCGUCCACUGACAGUCUGACUCCCGAGCACCAGCCCAUUGCCCAGGGAUGUUCUGAUUCCUUGGAGUCCAUCCCUGCGGGACAGGCAGCUUCCGAUGAUUUAAGGGACGUGCCAGGAGCUGUUGGUGGUGCAAGCCCAGAACAUGCCGAGCCGGAGGUCCAGGUGGUGCCGGGGUCUGGCCAGAUCAUCUUCCUGCCCUUCACCUGCAUUGGCUACACGGCCACCAAUCAGGACUUCAUCCAGCGCCUGAGCACACUGAUCCGGCAGGCCAUCGAGCGGCAGCUGCCUGCCUGGAUCGAGGCUGCCAACCAGCGGGAGGAGGGCCAGGGUGAACAGGGCGAGGAGGAGGAUGAGGAGGAGGAAGAAGAGGAGGACGUGGCUGAGAACCGCUACUUUGAAAUGGGGCCCCCAGACGUGGAGGAGGAGGAGGGAGGAGGCCAGGGGGAGGAAGAGGAGGAGGAAGAGGAGGAUGAAGAGGCCGAGGAGGAGCGCCUGGCUCUGGAAUGGGCCCUGGGCGCGGACGAGGACUUCCUGCUGGAGCACAUCCGCAUCCUCAAGGUGCUGUGGUGCUUCCUGAUCCAUGUGCAGGGCAGUAUCCGCCAGUUCGCCGCCUGCCUUGUGCUCACCGACUUCGGCAUCGCAGUCUUCGAGAUCCCGCACCAGGAGUCUCGGGGCAGCAGCCAGCACAUCCUCUCCUCCCUGCGCUUUGUCUUUUGCUUCCCGCAUGGCGACCUCACCGAGUUUGGCUUCCUCAUGCCGGAGCUGUGUCUGGUGCUCAAGGUACGGCACAGUGAGAACACGCUCUUCAUUAUCUCGGACGCCGCCAACCUGCACGAGUUCCACGCGGACCUGCGCUCAUGCUUUGCACCCCAGCACAUGGCCAUGCUGUGUAGCCCCAUCCUCUACGGCAGCCACACCAGCCUGCAGGAGUUCCUGCGCCAGCUGCUCACCUUCUACAAGGUGGCUGGCGGCUGCCAGGAGCGCAGCCAGGGCUGCUUCCCCGUCUACCUGGUCUACAGUGACAAGCGCAUGGUGCAGACGGCCGCCGGGGACUACUCAGGCAACAUCGAGUGGGCCAGCUGCACACUCUGUUCAGCCGUGCGGCGCUCCUGCUGCGCGCCCUCUGAGGCCGUCAAGUCCGCCGCCAUCCCCUACUGGCUGUUGCUCACGCCCCAGCACCUCAACGUCAUCAAGGCCGACUUCAACCCCAUGCCCAACCGUGGCACCCACAACUGUCGCAACCGCAACAGCUUCAAGCUCAGCCGUGUGCCGCUCUCCACCGUGCUGCUGGACCCCACACGCAGCUGUACCCAGCCUCGGGGCGCCUUUGCUGAUGGCCACGUGCUAGAGCUGCUCGUGGGGUACCGCUUUGUCACUGCCAUCUUCGUGCUGCCCCACGAGAAGUUCCACUUCCUGCGCGUCUACAACCAGCUGCGGGCCUCGCUGCAGGACCUGAAGACUGUGGUCAUCGCCAAGACCCCCGGGACGGGAGGCAGCCCCCAGGGCUCCUUUGCGGAUGGCCAGCCUGCCGAGCGCAGGGCCAGCAAUGACCAGCGUCCCCAGGAGGUCCCAGCAGAGGCUCUGGCCCCGGCCCCAGCGGAAGUCCCAGCUCCAGCCCCUGCAGCAGCCUCAGCCUCAGGCCCAGCGAAGACUCCGGCCCCAGCAGAGGCCUCAACUUCAGCUUUGGUCCCAGAGGAGACGCCAGUGGAAGCUCCAGCCCCACCCCCAGCCGAGGCCCCUGCCCAGUACCCGAGUGAGCACCUCAUCCAGGCCACCUCGGAGGAGAAUCAGAUCCCCUCGCACUUGCCUGCCUGCCCGUCGCUCCGGCACGUCGCCAGCCUGCGGGGCAGCGCCAUCAUCGAGCUCUUCCACAGCAGCAUUGCUGAGGUUGAAAACGAGGAGCUGAGGCACCUCAUGUGGUCCUCGGUGGUGUUCUACCAGACCCCAGGGCUGGAGGUGACUGCCUGCGUGCUGCUCUCCACCAAGGCUGUGUACUUUGUGCUCCACGACGGCCUCCGCCGCUACUUCUCAGAGCCACUGCAGGAUUUCUGGCAUCAGAAAAACACCGACUACAACAACAGCCCUUUCCACAUCUCCCAGUGCUUCGUGCUAAAGCUUAGUGACCUGCAGUCAGUCAAUGUGGGGCUUUUCGACCAGCAUUUCCGGCUGACGGGUUCCACCCCGAUGCAGGUGGUCACGUGCUUGACGCGGGACAGCUACCUGACGCACUGCUUCCUCCAGCACCUCAUGGUCGUGCUGUCCUCUCUGGAACGCACGCCCUCGCCGGAGCCUGUUGACAAGGACUUCUACUCCGAGUUUGGGAACAAGACCACAGGGAAGAUGGAGAACUACGAGCUGAUCCACUCUAGUCGCGUCAAGUUUACCUACCCCAGUGAGGAGGAGAUUGGGGACCUGACGUUCACUGUGGCCCAAAAGAUGGCUGAGCCAGAGAAGGCCCCAGCCCUCAGCAUCCUGCUGUACGUGCAGGCCUUCCAGGUGGGCAUGCCACCCCCUGGGUGCUGCAGGGGCCCCCUGCGCCCCAAGACACUCCUGCUCACCAGCUCCGAGAUCUUCCUCCUGGAUGAGGACUGUGUCCACUACCCACUGCCCGAGUUUGCCAAAGAGCCGCCGCAGAGAGACAGGUACCGGCUGGACGAUGGCCGCCGCGUCCGGGACCUGGACCGAGUGCUCAUGGGCUACCAGACCUACCCGCAGGCCCUCACCCUCGUCUUCGAUGACGUGCAAGGUCAUGACCUCAUGGGCAGUGUCACCCUGGACCACUUUGGGGAGGUGCCAGGUGGCCCGGCUAGAGCCAGCCAGGGCCGUGAAGUCCAGUGGCAGGUGUUUGUCCCCAGUGCUGAGAGCAGAGAGAAGCUCAUCUCGCUGUUGGCUCGCCAGUGGGAGGCCCUGUGUGGCCGUGAGCUGCCUGUCGAGCUCACCGGCUAGCCCAGGCCACAGCCAGCCUGUCGUGUCCAGCCUGACGCCUACUGGGGCAGGGCAGCAGGCUUUUGUGUUCUCUAAAAAUGUUUUAUCCUCCCUUUGGUACCUUAAUUUGACUGUCCUCGCAGAGAAUGUGAACAUGUGUGUGUGUUGUGUUAAUUCUUUCUCAUGUUGGGAGUGAGAAUGCCGGGCCCCUCAGGGCUGUCGGUGUGCUGUCAGCCUCCCACAGGUGGUACAGCCGUGCACACCAGUGUCGUGUCUGCUGUUGUGGGACCGUUGUUAACACGUGACACUGUGGGUCUGACUUUCUCUUCUACACGUCCUUUCCUGAAGUGUCGAGUCCAGUCCUUUGUUGCUGUUGCUGUUGCUGUUGCUGUUGCUGUUGCUGUUGGCAUCUUGCUGCUAAUCCUGAGGCUGGUAGCAGAAUGCACAUUGGAAGCUCCCACCCCAUAUUGUUCUUCAAAGUGGAGGUCUCCCCUGAUCCAGACAAGUGGGAGAGCCCGUGGGGGCAGGGGACCUGGAGCUGCCAGCACCAAGCGUGAUUCCUGCUGCCUGUAUUCUCUAUUCCAAUAAAGCAGAGUUUGACACCGUC